AAUCCUUACGGAGAAGCGGGAGUUUCGGCUGCAGGUUUUGGCUCUGCCGGCGCGCACGUAACCAGGAAACUGGGAGCCACGCGCAGCUCCCCGUCGACGCCGCCUUCAGAAGCCGCUGUGCACUGCGCUGCUGCCGCCUCGGCGCCGGGGAACGCAAGUUCCUUUACCUCGCGCGCAGUCGCCCGCCUCCCAACCCGGGAGGUGAAGGCGGGGACGGCGAGCGCGAACUCGAGGGGAUGGCUGUCCCGAGUGGCAACGGCCGAGCCCGGCCCGCGCAGGGACCCUUGUGGAGGGGCCCUCGGGGAGAGGCCGCAGCACGCUGGGGUCGUCACGCUGGUCCACGCCGGGCUCUCCUCCCGGGAGAGCGGACCCGGCCGCGUGCGAUUCGGACCCGCGGGGCUGGUGAAGCCGCUGUCCGGCCCCGCGGGUGCUGUCGGGCGUGCGUCACUGCUUUUUGUAGAACAUGACCUGACUUCCGAUGGCAGCUACUGACGUCAGAGCUGCUCCCUAGACUCUCCCUAAGCGUCUUUCCAGAAGGAUCUGCUUAGAAACCAAAGCUCCAGCCGAGUGUUUCUUUUCCCCUACAUUUUUAGUGAUUCCCUUCUGUUGAUGCCUUUGAAAGCUCGGAGAAAUAAAUACGUUUAUUGUUAUGCUGUUAGAAAACAAGUUCAUGCUUGUCCUCUAAAGAUAAGUGGUCUUUUCAUUCUACUUUUUGUUUUGUAGUAAGAGCCAUAAAAUUUGCAAUCGCAAGUUUAUGUUGUUAUACUUAGUUACCCAAGGGGUAGUUUUAAGCAUUUUUAUUCAUAUGAAUAUUUGAAUAUAAAUGUGUGUUCAAAUAUAUAGAAUCGUUCUUAUAUUCCACAUUUUUAAUAUUUAAACUAUUCACAAUAUCUUUUAAUGAUGUUUAAAGAACGGCAGUGUAGAGAUACUGUUGUCAGAUUUGUGAGGUGAGCACACGUUGAUAUUGCCAGUUUCGCUUUUGUUUAUCAAUUCAAUAAGCACUGCUUUUUAAAACACGUGUUGAAGCUUCAGGUUUGCACAGAAGUUCAUUUUCAGGAAUUCCUAACUAAUAAAGGGUAUCAGACACGUUCUUACAGUUUUGAACAUAAAUACUGCAGUUAGCAUAUGUAGUGGGAUAUUUGUGUGGUGAAAGUGCCUCCAUAUUUCAUAUCUUUUCUUUGAAACAAGAUUCUGUUCAGUAUGCAUUAAGUGGUAGUUAUUUUUUAACUUCCUGUUACAUACGUAAAUUUCAUAAGGAAAGGAAAUUUGGGGAGUCGUUACAGCUUUUCUCCCUUUAAUCACAGCGUACCUGUCCAUUGCUCACAUUGUUUUCAGAAAAAAAAGUUGUAUCUCAGCUGGAUAUCUGACUUGACUUUAGUAAUGGGCCUAGAAACUAUAAACUGAACAAAGCUUAUAAUGCACAAAAACAGGAUAAGUACAUUUGGGGGACAAUAUCUUACUGGCAAGUAACUGGAGUUUCACCAGGCGUGUAGCAGGUGGGAUCAAUUUUCUAAAACGGAAGAUGAUCUAAGAUGCAUAUUUUAUAGGCGUUCUCCUAAGCAGUGCUAAUUCUACAUGUUUUAAUUGCUGGUAGAUGCGUUUCCAGAACGAGGAUGCCAUUUACAGCGAGUGUUAAAAAAAACGUUGGAUGAUGAGUAAGUGACCGAAUAGAUGAGAGAUGUGUGGGCUGAAUCUUGAGUAGUAAGAGUUUGCUAAGGAGUCCAGGAAGGGAAGAGUAUUUCUAAGAAGUGUAAAAUAUCUUCCAGUAUUGAGAGCACUAUAUGUAGUUCAGUCUGGGGGCAGUGUGUGAUACACAUGCAGCUGUGAUGUGAAAUAGAGAAAGGCCGACAAAUGAGAAAGUAUUAACCACUAACGUCUAUUCCAGUUUAUUAUAUUACAAAUUGACAUUAAUUGAGCACUUGUGCCUCAAGACUAACGCUCAUAGGUAUUAUCUGCAUUUUACAGAAGAGGAAAUUGAGGCUUAGGGAGAUCCAUUAACUUGUCAUGUAAUUAUUAGCAGGUAAAUCAGGAAUUUGAAGUCAGUUUGACUCCAGAGCCCACAUUCUUAUACCUAUGUGUUUUAAAUAAUUUUGGUCACCUCUGGUCAAUUCAGGCUAAGAUUGGUUUCUUUAAUGCAAACCAAAGGCCUUUUUUUUUUUUUUUUUUUUUAACUCUGAAACACAAUCUCGCUGUCUUGCCCAGAUUGGAAUGCAGUGGCGUGAUCUCAGCUCACUGCAACCUCCGUCUUCCCGGGUUCAAGUGAUUCUCGUGCGUCAGCCACCCAAGUAGCUGGGCUUACAGCUAUACGCCACCACACCCAGCUAAUUUUUGUAUUUUCAGUAGAGAUGGGUUUCACUGUGUUGCCCAGGCUGGUCUCAAACGCCUGACCUCCAGUGAUCCACCUGCCUUGGCCUUCCAAAAUGUUGGGAUUACAGGCAUGAGCCACCAUGCCUGGCCGCAAAAGAGUCUUCAGAGAAAAUUAUUGUAAUCCAUAGAAAAAACAACUGUUUUAUUUAAUAAUGACUGUCAGUGUAGCCUUGUUCCUGGAAUUGAAUCUCCCGCAAUACUAAACCUAGUACUUCUUAUUCAAGUAAUUACUCUUGAGGGUCAGGCGCGGUGGUGGCUCACGUCUGUAAUCCCAGCACUUUGGGAGGCUGAGGCAGGCCGAUCGCCUGAGGUCAGCAGUUUGAGACCAGAAUGGCCAACAUGGUGAAACCCCGUCUCUACUAAAAAUAGAAAAAUUGGCCGGGCGUGGUGGCAGGUGCCUGUAAUCCCAGUUACUCCGGAGGCUGAGGCAGGAGAAUCGCCUGAACCUGAGAGGCGGAGGUUGCAGUGAGCCGAGAUUGCGCCACUGCACUCCAGCCUGGGUGACAAGAGCAAGAUUCCGUCUCAAAAAAAAAAAAAGGAAAAGAAAAAGUAAUUACUCUUGCAUCAGUGAAUUGUGCCAGGUGAAAAUUAUUAAAAGUAGUUGGUGGAACCGAUAAGCUAAUUUUAUCUAUUUCUUGCUUGCUGUGGUUUUCCUGUUUCUUAUUGACCAAGAAAACACUGGAAAGCAUUACCAAAAGGCACAGUAUUGAAAGGAGGAGUAAUUGAGAAUACCUACUCAUUCCUACUUUAAAACAUUAAUUGGAUUGUAUAUGUUUAGUAAUGCCAUAGAAAACUUCAGCUCUAAAGCAAGUGAAAUAAUGUAAAACUAAAAAUCUCACCAGAUGCAGUGGCUCACGCCUGUAAUCCCAACACUUUGGGAGGCUGAGGCAGGCAGAUCACUUGUGGCCAGGAGUUCGAGAUCAGCCUGGCCAACAUGGCGGAACCGUCUCUACUAAAAAUACAAAAAUUAGCCAGGUGUGUGGUGCGUGCCUGUAAUGCCAGCUACUUGAGAGGCUGAGGUGGGAGAAUCACUUGAACCCAGGAAGCAGAGGUUGCAGUGAGCCGAGAUCGUGCCACUGCACUCCAGCCUGGGUGACCGAGUGAGGCCUCAUCUCCAAAAAUACUGAAAACUAAAAAUCCCAGUAGCUGGCCUGGUUUCACAUGUAUUUUUUAAAUCCCUUGAGAAUAUCAUAACGCCAAAGCAUUGAAGUCAAACGCAUCAAGCAUUUCUGAAUAUGAUGUCUUGUUUAUUGCCAGCCAGGCACCCAUGGUAUAUCAAUGCUGACCAGAGUCCACUGAGCCUUAGAAGUAACGAUAUUUUAAUUAAUAAUGAUAUUAUGGCAAUAAUACUUCUAUCGUUCAUACACUGAAGGUGAUAAUAUUCCAAAUAUGACAACUUUUCAAAGACAGAAGGUUAUAACCAGAUCUGGAAUUUCCAUAGAUUUUUUUUAAGUUUUUUUUUUUAAACAUCUACAGAUUUAAGAUGACUUGAAUUAAUCAAAUAUAAUUCUGGGCUUCAUUGCAAUGCCACUGUCAAGAAACCCAUUACCCUAAUAAUUGUAAAAACGGAAGAAUUUCUUACAAAGAAAUUCUUUCUCUUUAACAUAAAUUCUUCCAGCCUUGAUAACUCAAACUUCUUGGGGAAGAUGAUAAAUUGGAUAGUUAUUCUAAACAACUGCUGCAACAGGAUAUUGUGGCAAAAAGAAAAGGCAAAGUAUAGUUAUCCUCUUUUGAUGAUGUUUACUUUCCUGAGAGCCUGUAAUCAGAAGGGUCCAGUGGUCUCAAUGGUGACUAGAUUUAAAUGUUCACUUCUUCACUGUUGUGAUAAGAACUUGGAGAACUUGAAAGGUAUUUCAUAUUUUUGUUAUUUCUCCUCCUGGUUAUAUAUUCCUUUCAAUGAAAUGUGGAAAUUACAGAUGAUAAAUUUGUAAAAUUAGAUGAAGUAGAGAAAAAGGUAGAAAGUUAGUCCUUAAUAUUAAACCAAUUGAUGGAGGGAGCCAAGUUUCUUAUUGUUGGAGAGGGAAGUUACAGAUUAGUAGAAAAGGCUAAAAUGAGCCAGGUAGUAAUGGAUUUGUCCAAGAUGUCAAUAAGAAUUCAUAGUUAGCUUAAUAUAGAUUCAGAUGGAUAGAAGCAGAAAUAAUUAUAGGUGUGUGUGUAUACAUGGGUUAUGCAUAUACAUAUGUCCUAGCUCUGCCUGCUGUGAGAGGGCCUAAAGCAGUGACACCGCAGUAACAAUGAACACACCCAGUACCCAGAUCCGGGUUUCUAAUACCAUUCUCUAGUGAAAGAAACCAGGGCUCCUUGCAGACAUUGCUGAUUCUGGGGCUGGGGCAGGGAAAAUACAAGAUGAGCCUAGAGCAUCGUGUAGUACCAGAACAAGGUACUGGUACUUGUUCCAGUAAGUGGAAGGAUAGGACAUGUGAAAGGGACCCAGGAGCUAACCUGAAAGAGCUCCCAAUGGCCAAAACUGGAACUAACUCAGGUACUGUUGGAUUAUAACUCAGUACAUAGUUAUCCAUGAGUCUAUACUGAUAUAAACAACUGAAUGAAUAAAUAAAUAAAUGGGAGAUGGGAGACAGAAGACAAUGCUUCUUUACAGAAGAAUUUCAAAUGUUUAAUGUAGAUAUUCCCUGGUGAAGACGAUUCCGCCUCCAACGCCUUCUUGAAUGUGGGCUACACAUAAUGACUUGCUUCCAAAAAGUAGAGUAUGGGAAGGGGAAAACGAAGCGACUUUACAGUGGAGAAGCCUGUUGGAUGCUGCCAUGGCCAGUAAUUGUUCACAUCCUCAGUGGAAAGUCCUGUUGAUGAUGUGAUUGUUGACACGAUGUGAUGAGAAGGCCACUUCACCUCUUCGGUAUUCUUCCCUAAAACCCAUAGCCCAGUCUAAUCAUGAGUAAAACAGAUGAAUGUUGAUUGGGGACAUUCUUUAGGAUACACGGCUAGUAUUCCUCAAAACUGUGAAGGUUAUGAAAAACAAGGGAAGUUUGAGAAACUGCCGCAGACCAGAAGAGGCUCAGGAGGCAUGGUGACUGACUCUAGUGUGUUCACUUGGAUGGGAUCCUGGCACAGCAAAAGAACGUCAGUGGAAAGAUGAGUAAAAUCCUAAUAGAGUUUUAGGUAAUUUUCACGAACCAAUGUUGGUUUCCUAGUUGUGGCAAACAUACUAUUAUAAUGUGAUGUUAACAGUGGGGGACACUGAGGGACACUCUGUGGUAUCCUUGCAGCUUUUCUGUACAUCUCAAAUUAUUGUAAAACAUAAAGUGUACUUCAAAAAAGAGGAAUUGAGGCCACUUAAAGCUCUCACAGUGGCAGCGUUCUCACAGCUGUUUGGUCUGCUUAUCCAACACGCUUCAUUUCCUCGUAAGACGUGCCGACUGCCCAUUGCACUGACCGUUGGAAGACCGUAGGCAUUCUCUAGAAUGUCAGUCACUUGGGCUCACACCAGUUGAACUGUAUGCCUACCAAGAGUCAGUUUUUCUACACCUGUAAGGAUUAUUAUAAAAUGUAAUUCAAUUAAAUAUUUUUUCUUUUUUCUUUUUUUUUUUUUUGAGACGGAAUCUUGCUCUGUCACCCAGGCUGGAGUGCAGUGGCACCAUCUCAGCUCACUGUAACCUCUGCCUCCUAGGUUCAAGCGAUUCUCCUGCCUCAGCCUCCCUAGUAGCUGGGACUACAGGCAUGGGCUACUACGCCCAGCUAUUUUAUUUUUUUCUGUAUUUUUAGUAUAAACAGGAUUUCACCAUGUUGGUCAGGCUGGUCUUGAACUCCUGACCUCAAAUGAUCCACCUGCCUUGGCCUCUCAAAGUACUGGGAUUACAGGCGUGAGCCACCCUGCCCGGCCUCAAUUAAAUAUUAUGUAACUGAUGAGAUAUGAGUGAGACAUGAGAGCUUGUUUUUAAGAAAAUGAAUGCUUUCAAAGUCAAGUCACUACGAAAACUUGUUUCGAAGUAGAUGAGAAUAUUAAGUCAACUGUAAAAUAUGGGGGAAAGAAUUCUGUACUUGGAUUGUUUAUGGGCAUUUUAAAAUUUAAACUCCAUUUUAAAGAAACCUAAUCUGGAAUUCUUAUGCCCAUAGUUUAUGCAAGAAAACUCUAAAUUCUCACGGUUGAACACUAGUUAAAUCACUUCUGGCCCUAAAUGAGAAGAUUGGGAAAUAACUUUUUUUUACACGUUUUGGGUAUAAAGUGCACAUGGUAUUUUUGAACACUCUUUUAUUAAUCUCCACUGUCAUUCUUGUUUGACCACCUGCCACUCCCAAGAAUGCCAGGUCAGAGGGGUCCAAAUGUGUUUACUGUACAGUGUUUCUUUCACUUAAAGAAGGUAAGGACUGCAGAUGAACAGAUACGAAGGUUUGUAUUACCAACUGCACCUGCAUAAAAUUGGAUAACUAAAAAUGAUUUACUGGAUGAUUUGAGACACUCAAAAGUUUGAAACUCAGUUGUUUUUUUUUAGUGAAGGUCAUUUAAAGUGCCUGGAAAAUGUAGAAUACUAGAUAUAUACUCUGAAUAGAACUUAGCAUCAUAUAUUACAUUGUUAUUCACUUGUUUUAAUUAUUAUUUUAGGCUGGGCACGGUGGCUCACGCCUGUAAUCCCAGCACUUUGGGAGGCUGAGGUGGGCGGAUCACAAGGUCAGGAGUUCAAGACGAGUCUGGCCAACAUAGUGAAACCCCGUCUCUAUUAAAAAAUACAAAAAAAUUAGCCGGGUGUGGUGGUGUGCGCCUGCAAUCCCAGCUACUUGGGAGGCUGAGGUGGGAGAAUCACGUGAACCUGGGAGGUGGAGGUUGCAGUGAACCAAGAUUGCGCCAUUGCACUCCAGCCUGGGCAACAGUGUGAGACUCCGUUCUCAAAAUAAAUAAAUAAAAUAAAAAUAAAAAUAAAUAAAAAUUAAAAAAGGCCAGGUGUAGUGGCUCACAUCUGUAAUCUCAGCACUUUGGGAGGCCAAGGUGGGGUGGAUCACAAGGUCAGGAGAUCCAGACCAUCCUGGCCAACAUGGUGAAACCCUGUCUCUACUAAAAAUACAAAAAUUAGCUGGGUGUGGUGGCAGGCACUUGUAAUCCCAGCUACUUGGGAGGCUGAUUCAAGCAGGAGAAUUGCUUGAAUCCAGGAGGCGGAGGUUGCAGUGAGCCGAGAUCGCACCACUGUACUCCAGCCUGGCGACAGAGCAAGACUCUGUCUCAAAAAAAAUAAUAAUUAUUAUUAUUUUAUUAGUAAGAUUAGCAUUUUAUACUUUUUCUCCUCUUAGGAACAAAGAUUAAUUUGAGUAGGAUGUUAACACAUUUUGAGAAAUUUGAGUUAUUGUAAGGAAAUGUUUGUUGUGCAACCUAUUUUCUUCAUUUAAACAAUAUAAAGACAGUAGAUGAAUACAUAGCAUACCUUCAGAAACAGCAUGUACAUAUAUAAUUGAAAUAUUAUUUUUCUGUAUAAUUUAUCAUUUGAAACAUUUUCUUUCAACUGCUGUGAGAACACUGUCAGGUAGAAGAAGAAAAAGCUUAAGGUUUAUUCUUACCGAACCUGUGUUUACUAGAAGUCCUAGAUAGAUAGAUAGGUAGGUAGAUAGAUAGCCUAGGUAGGCCUGAUAGGUAGGCAGGCUAGGUAGGUUAGGCAGGUUAGGUAGGUAGGUAGGCAGAUAGGUAGAUAGAUAGUAAAAGGAAAAGGAAAUCUGGGAGCCCAAGAUCUUGAGUUAGUAGGUAGGCAGAAAUAAGACCCCGGGACAUGGCUAUAUCAAAGGUUUAAUUAAUAUUGGGAAUAAGGAUGAGAUGUUGCUUGUACAGCAGACUUGAUGGACUUGUCCCUCAGGAAACCAGCCUAACACGUUCUCAUCAGAUCAGAAGACCACUGCGCUGCUCUCACCUCAGACUUCAUCUCCUACCAUGUGGGAUGUGAGAAGCCACCUCCCUAAUUUCUGAGUCCGAAUCUCUGCCUUACACGCCGUGGAACUCCUCCAUCAUCUGGGUUUCUAGCUGUGCCACAGGCCUGAAAAUAUUAGCUUAGGUUUAAAUUCAGUGAACUUAAGGGGCAGUCUACACACCACGGGGGCAUCCCCUAGGGCCGGCCUGUCCUCGGCCUACUGCGUCGCUUUUCCUGUCGAGGGCUCGUCACACAGCCUUUCCACUUCCACGGGACAGUGGGGAAAAGGAGUUAGAGAGGGAGGAAUCAUAUCCAGAGGCCUUCAUUCCACCCCUGCCUCAGAACCCAAGUUGGGAGAGAGCUUUCAAGGCACGGAGACGUGGGAGAAGGCCCGGGGCUGGGGGCUGGCUUCUCGAGCUCUGGUGUGAAGACGCUGCCCACCUCUGCAAGAACCCGUUAUCCAGCGGGGUGGGGACCUUGUGGGGAAUAUGGAGCUGCUGUAGGCAAGGACAGAUAGCCUUAUGGCUGUCCAUCUGUGGCCAAUGGCAGUAUGUUUGUAACCUCACCACAAUAUUAUUACAGAAAAUUUGAGAAAUAGAGAAGAGAAACAUGCAGGUCCACAGUCUCUUACUUGCAAUUCAAAAAGACAUGAGGGUCUGAAACACAGUAUGUUUAUAAUUCUUAAGGCAGCAAGAUCAUCUUAGCUGCACACGCCUGAGACUGUAUUUAGUGUUUAUUCCAUUUUGUGUGAACAGUGUUAUAUUUUACUGCAGAAACACAACUAUGGCAAAAGGGUGCAAUUCUAGACCAUGCCCAGGCGGUUCUGCAGUAGGGUGUACAUGUGUUAUAUGUUAUUUGUACAUUGUGUGGCAUUUCCAAAAUCCAAACACGUCUUAAUUCUAAAACAUUUCUGUUCCCAAGGUUUCGGAUACGGCCUUAUAUACCUGCACAUAAUCCACAGUUCACACGGUGGUUUUUUGUUGGUUUGUUUGAGACUGAGUCUCGCUCUGUCACCCAGGCUGCAGUGCGGGGGCGCAAUCUCGGCUCACUGCAGUCUCUGCCCCUCGUCUCAUGCCUCAGGCUCCCGAGUAGCUGGGAUGACAGGCACCCACCACUAGCCCAGCUAAUUUUUGUAUUUUUAGUAGACACGGGGUUUCACCAUGUUGGCCAGGCUGGUCUCGAACUCCUAACCUCAGGUGAUCUGCCCACCUUGGCCUCCCAAAGUGCUGGGAUUACAGGCAUGAGCCACUGCACCCUGCCAACACAAUGGUUUUGAUGUGUUUACACAUAGGGUCUUUUCUCCCCUUGCUUCUUUACUUUUAUAUAAUAGUAAACAUCAUGUACGUACAUGUCUCCACGGCAUCCACUUGCCUCUGUCCUCAGCUCAGUGGCCUUCGUAGUGCUGGUGCCUCAGCUUGUCACCACUAGCUAGUCCUUUCAGUAAGUCCAAAGCAACUACAUUUCUACUGACUCCUCCGUUUACAAGAGUCCCAGGCACUGCUGGAGGGUGUAGUCUCUUAAGGUCCAGGGGUCACGUUGGGGUGUACCUGUCUCCUAUAGCCAAAAGUUUGGGCCAGGACUAGUGAGGAUGCAGCUUGUGCAAAGACUAAAACACCAUCAGGCAGCUUUUCCAAAGCACAGAAAUGGCUGGAAUCCACCUGCCCCAUGCCCUUAAGAGCACUGAGGUAGGCUGGAGCCCAGCCUUUUCUCUUGUCCUCUCUGCCCACCACUUUCUGGGCCUCUGACUGAUGCCUGGAUUUUUAAAAUUAGUAUUUAAAAUGUUAAUAGUUUUUUGCAUAUAGGUCAUAGACACUUAUCUGAGGUUAUUCCCACAUAGUUUAUAUUUUUGUGUUAUUACAAAUGAGCAUUCCUUGCCCAGUGUACUUUCUCACUGGCUAUGAAAGAUAUGCUUUUCAUUUUUGUUCAUUUAUUUCAUACCCUGCCACUCUCCUGAGCUAAUCAUAUCAGGCAGCCUUUAAGCUGAUCCCUUUGGAUUCCCAGAGAUCCAAUCAUCAUGUACAAGAAAGAUAAUUAUGCUUCUUUUUAAAAUAUAUCUUGCUUGUUUUGUGUUUUAUUUUUUGUCCAGAACUUCUCAAAUGUGACUGCAUAAUAAUGGUGAUACCACGACUCUUUGUUUUGUUUUUCAUUUCAGUUAGACUACUGCAUUUUCCUCUCUGAAUGUAACUUCUCUCUGUCUUGCUCUAAAUUGAAAUCUGUAUCUUCCCUGAGAAAGACACAACUUCCCCUGAAGAUAAGGCUGCAGACACCUUGAGCUUGACAGUAUAAGAUGAUGUUAUUUCUUUAUCUCCCCCCCCCCCUCCCCGAGACAGAGUCUUGCUCUGUCACCCAGGCUGGAGUGCAGUGGCACGAUCUCAGCUCACUGCAACCUCCACCUUCCGGGUUUGAGCAAUUCUCCUGCCUCAGCCUCCCGAGUAGCUGGGAUUACAGGCGCCUACUACCGCACCCAGCUAAUUUUUGUAUUGUUAGUAGAGACGGAGUUUCACCUUUUUGGCCAGGCUGGUCCUGAACUCCUGACCUCCUGAUCUGCCUGCCUUAGCCUCACAAAGUGCUGGGAUUACAGGCAUGAGCCACCGCGCCUGGCCUGGGAUGAUGUUACUAUACAUUCAGUUUGUCCAAGGACAUGGGGAGGUGGGGUGACAAGCAACGUUAAUGGGGCUGCAAAUGAAUAUUUUAUAAAAGAUUUAUCUGGUUUUUCUGUUCAGUGUGGCUCUCAUACUCUAGGACAGAGGUCAAUUUAAAUUUUGGUUGUGACAGAUUUUUUUCAAUUCUCUUUGCGACCCUGAUUUUGUCAAUUCUUUUUAUGAUUUAUGUCACACUUGGAUAGUGAUGAGCAAUUAUCACAUACUUUAAGGAAUUCUACUCAUGUAUUUUACUAGCUGACCUCCGGGGGUAAAUCAUCCCGGAGUGUAUUUAUAACUGUAACAGUAUCGGCUCCAGAGAAGACCCGGCAGCUGUAACUGCCAACAAGGUUUCCCCAUUGGGAACAGAACAAAUAGACGUGUGGGCCCACACAAACGGCGGGAAGAUUUUGAACGUAUCAGUGUUUCUUAGCCUGUUUUAUUUGAUCACAGAAUACAUGGUAAAUCAGAGAAAAAUAAAAUCAAAAGCUACUGGACUCUUUCAUCCCGUGCUUGCCACAGCUUAUCUGGUCAUAAAACACAUCCUGUCUUUCCCCACACUUUUCCUCUCUUCAGGGCCUGAUGGUGUAAAUCUGCCACACCCAAAAGGAAGGGGUGGGAAAAAAGCACUUUUGUUUUAAACACACAAACGGACCUAGCUGAAAGGGGCGGCGGGGGACGGGGGGCGGGGAGGGGGAUGCAGGGCGGAGUGGGAAGAACAGAAAGCUACUGCCUGAAUCAGUAUUGUCUUUUGAGAUCUCAGUAAGUUAUUCUCUUCUAAUUUUUCAUCAUAUAUGUGUAGAUGGUGUUUCCAAUUACUAUAUGAACACUAUGGGGUUUUUAAAAAACUACUGUUAGGCAAUAGUAAUGAAAGGAAAAAUAACAAUAAACACGGGUUUGAGGGUUUGCCGGGGAGGCUUAUUUAUCUCUGUUUUCUUGGGCACUAGGAACAUUAUCUAGUAUGAAAGGAACUUCAGUGUUGAACCUCAAUUUUAAAAGAACUUUAAAUACAGCUAUUCAUUAUUUCAUUUCAACAUUGGAUUAGGCCAACUAUUAAGUGUCAAAAGAGCCAGUCAGAAGCAUCAGCAAAUGUAAUUAAUUUUAAAAACCCAGAAACUUUAAACACUUGGCCCAUUGAAAGUUAAAUGGAAUGUCUAGGCUCCUAUUUAUAUGACAUAGUCUAGGGUGGUGUUUUAGUCUGUUCCUCCUUCUAUAACAAAAUUCCUUAGUUGGGUAAUUUAUAAACAAUCGAAAUUGAUUUCUCAUAGUUCUGGAGGUUGGGAAGUCCAAAAUCAAGGCACUGGCAGAUUCAGUGUCUGGUGAGAGCUUUCAGGACAGUGCCUUGUUGUGUCCUCACAUGGCAGAAGGCAGAAUGGCAAAAGAGUGAGCUCUCUGCAUCUAACCCUUUCCUAAGGGCACAAAUCCCAUCCUUAAGAGCAGAACCCUCCCGUCACUCCCCAGGGCUCCACCUCUUAAUACCAUCACCUUAGGGGGUUAAGUUUCAACAUGUGAACUUUGGAGGGACACACACUCUAAGCAUAGCAGGUACUGUGUCAGGACUAGGACUCAGCAUAUAGUUGUACUCAUGGGCAACAGUUAUUACAGCAAAGGAAUACACAACAAGAUUAGCAACAACAACAAAGGCACAGGUGGAAUCUGAAGAAAUCCACGCCCAGGCUUAUGUUCUCUCCCUUCCAUGAGGAAAAACACGGCGCACCUGCCUGUCUCCAGUAGUGAAGAAUGCAGGGACAUGGGCACAGUGUUUGUCCCAAAGGAAGCCCGGAGGGAUGUUUUUGUUGGGGGCAAGUCAUGUAGGCAUCCUCUGCCUAGCAGCUACCAAAAUGACAGAAUUCCACAAGGAAAGCAGAUAGUCACCACAAAUCACAUUGUUUAUGCAACAGUUUAAACACAGCAAAACCAGUCUUACCAGUUAGGGGAUGGAAGUGCCAAGUUCCUGAUGUCAGCCAAAUGCCAGCCUUGCCAGUAUGCCCUUGUAAAGAUGGCAGCCUCGGGCCUGCCGUGGUAACUGUUUUCUGCACAGGCACACAACCCACAAACGACACUAACAUACUUAAGACACAUUUUGCAGCAGCAGUGUGUUUUUGGAGAUGGGGUCUCACUCUGUCACCCAGGUUGGAGUGCAAUGGCACAGUCAUAGCUCAUUGCAGCCUCAAACUCCAGGGCUCAAGGGAUCUUCCCCCCUCAGCCUCCUGAGUAGCUAGGACUAUAGGUGUGCACCACCACACCUGGCUAAUUUUUUUAUUUUUAAUUUUUUUGGAAGGACAGGGCCUCACUACGUUGCCCUGUCUGGUCUUGAACUUGUGGCCUCAAGUGAUCCUCCCACCUUGAUCUCCCAAAGUUCUGGGAUUACAGGAAUGAACCACCACACCCAGCCUGAAUACAGUUAGAUGGUUCAGAGCACAAAGUUUAAAUGCAAGGUUGCCUAUAAAAGAUUUAAUAUACAUACUUCAAAACACAACUACUGAGGUGAAAGUAUAACAAAUGAUGAGGGAAGAAUGAUCUUUUCAACAAACAGGUACUGGGCAAAUGGAUAUCCACAUGCAAAAGAACUGAUUUGGACCUUUCCCUCAUACACAGAAUGAACUCAAUGGAUCAAAGACCUAAAUGUAAGAGUAAAUAUAAAACUCUUAGAAGAAGGCACAGGGGUAAACUUUUGUGACCUUGGAUUAGGCAAUGGUUUCUUUUAGAUGUGACACCUAAAGCACAGGCAAGAAAAGAAAAAAUAGAAAAACUGGACUUCAUUAAAAAUAAAAGGUUUUGGGAUCAAAAGAAACUGUUAAAGAAAAACAUCCACACAUUGGGAAAAAAUUGCAAAUUAUACACUGGUAUGAGACUAGUAUGUAGGAUAUAUAAAGAACUAUUAUAACCCAACUGGAAAAUGGGCAAAAGCUUUGAAUAGACAUUUACAAAUACAAAUGCAAAAUGGGUAAGAAGCACAGGAAAAGAUGCUCAACAUGAUUUUUCAUUAGAGAAAUGCAAAUCAAAACAACAAUGAGAUAGCGCUUCACAUCCACUAGGAUGGUGAUAAUAAAGAUAGGCAACAACAGGUGUUGGUGAGGAUGUAGAACCUUAUACACUAUUGGUAGGGAUGUGAAAUGGUACAACCACUUUGAAAUACAGAUUGGCAAUUUCCCAAAAUGUCAAACAUAGAAUUACCAUAUGACCCAGCAAUUCCACUCCUAGGUACAUACCCAAGAGAAUUGAAAACAUGUAUCCUCACAAAAACUAGUACGCAGACGUUUGUUGCAGCACUAUUCAUAAUAGGCCAAAGCUGGAAACAAUCCAAGUGCUUAUCAACUGAUGAACAGAUUUUUUAAAAAUCCAUAUAAUGAAAUGUUAAUCAUCCAUAAAAAGGAAUGAAAUAUUGAUACAUGCAACAAAGUACAUGAAUGUUGUAAACAUUAUGCUAAGUGAAAGAAGCCAGACAUAAAAGGCCACAUAUUCUAUGAUUCCAUUUAUAUAGAAUAUCCAAAAUAGGCAAAUCCAUAGAGACAGAAAGUAGAUUAGUGUUUGCCAGGAACUGAAGGGAGGAGAAUGGGGAGUGGCUGCCGAUGCUACAGUGUUUCUUCUGGAUGAUGAAAAGGUUUUGGAAUUCCAUAGCGGUAAUUAUUGCACAACUUUGUAAUUAUAUUAAAAACCUCUGAAUUGUACACUUUAAAAGGGUGAAUUUUAUGGUAUGUGAAUUAUAUAUCAAUUUGUAAAAAGUGUAACAAAUGGAUUAACAUAAAUGUUAAUUCAGGAAAUCAGAAGUAUAAAGAUGCAGGAUGAGCCAUACAAUAAUUUCCUCACAUUCUUCUGAGGAACAGACUGAAGCCCCCCAAAACAGCUGUAGUUUCCUGUCCCUCUUUGGAAAUAGCCAGGACUCUUCAGCCUGAAUUAGAGGCUGUCUCAUACUUGUCAUAGUCAGGACAACUAAAAACUUUUUACUAGGACUCCUGAAAAGUCAGCCUAAUUGAAUGGGUGAUUUAUAUUCAGAACUCAAAUGAACCAAGCAGUCUUCCCAUAAAUUACUCAAACUACCAGAAAUCUAAAUCAGCAAUUAAUUUAAAAAGGGAUUUUGUGCCCAAUCACUUGGAAACUAUUUGGCAGUAUCUACAAAAGCUGACUAUGCAUAGUCAUUGACCCAGUAACUACUACUACUAUGUUUAUCCGCAACAAAAACAUGUAUAAAUUUUCAGGAAAAAGCAGGCCCAAGAAUGUUCCUAAUCGUCCAAAACAGAAGCUACCCAAAGUCCAUCAAGUAGAAAAGAUAAAUUGUGAUAUAUUCACACAAUGUAAUACAACAAUAUGAAGGAAAAAAAUUACAACUAACACAACAAAAUGGAUGAAUCAAUGUCAAGGGAAAGAAGCUAGACACAAAAUAUUACACACUGUAUGAUUCCAUUUAUAUAGUGUAAAAAACAAGAAAAAGUAACUUGUGCCAUUACAGGUGCAUAUAGGAUUUACACUUGAGUUCAUGUAGUGACUAGAAGGGAAUACAACAGGACUUCCAAAGUGCUGGUAAGGAUCUCUUUCUUGAUCUGAGAGCUAGUUACAUGGAUGUGUUUGGCUUGUGAAAAUCUAUCAAGCUGUAAACUUACAUAUACAUUUCUGUAUCUUUCAUUUACUUCAGUAAACAGUUUUUAAAUGGAUUGCUUUAAUGGCAGACUAGAUGUGGCUAAAGAGAGAAUUAAUAAAAAGGGAGAGAUUACUGAAGAGAUUACCCAGAGUGUGUCAGAGAGAAAAAAAACGAUGGAAAAUCUGAAAGGCAAAUUUAAGAGACAUGAGGAGAAGGUCUUAUCAAAAUGCUGGAGAGAAAAAUGAAAUAGAUUGGGGCCUCUGAAGAGCAUGGUGGGUUGACUUGUGUUUCCAACCAAAGAUAUAUCUGAGUGCUAACUCCUGAAACCUGUGAAUGUGAACCUCUUUGGAAAUAGGAUAUUUUACAUGUAAUCAAGUUAAGAGGAAGUCAUGUUGGAUUAGGGUGGGUGCCAACUCCAAUGACUGGUGUCCUCAUAAGAGGGAGGAGAGGACACACAGAGAUAGAGGAGACAUGAAGGGAAGGCCAUGUAAACACAGAGGCAGAGGUUGAGUUGUGCAACUACAAGCCUAGGAACACCAGACAUCACCAGAAACCACCAGAAGCUGGUGGGGAAUGCUUAGGAUGAUUUUUCCCUAGGGCCAGAGGAAGCAUGGCCCUGCCAACACCUUGAUUUUGGACUUCUAGGCUCCGGAACUGUGAGAGAGGAAAUUUCUGUUCUUUUAAGCCACAAAGUUUUUGAUAUUUUGUUUUAGCGGCCCCAGGAAACUAACAAACACAAAUAAAUUAUCCCUGAGAAUGUUUGGGAGCUAAUAAAAGACGCCAAUCCAAGACAGGAAGCUAAAAAUUCCCAAAACAUAAUAAAUAUCUAGUCAAUCCAAUAAAUACCCAGUAAAUCCAUCAAAAAGGCAAUAUUUAUUGUAUUGCCUGGACACGGUGACUCACUGCGGUAACCGCAGCACACUGGGAAGCUGAGACAGGAGGAUUGCUGGAGCCCAGGAACUUGAGACCAGCCUGCAUAACAUGGAGACCCCAUCUCUACAAAAAUUUUAAGGAAUUAGCUGGAUGUCAUGGCAUAUGCCUGUAGUCCCAAGUACUUGGGAGGCUGAGGUGGGUGGAUCACCUGAGCCCAAGAGGUUGAGGCUGCAGUUGAGAGCUAUGAUUGUACCAAUGCACUCUUCUAGCCUGGAUGACAGAGUGAGACGCUGUCUCAGAGAGAGAGAGAGAGAGAGAGAAGUGCGCAGGUGCUGGGACACGCCAGCUGUUCUGCUUACCUGUCCUUAACUAGCCCUGUGGCCUUGGGCAAGUUACUUAACUUCCCCACUGUCCCUUGGUUUCCCCAUACGUUAAACGAGCCUCAUAAUGAACCUUAUUUCGUAAAGUUUUGUCGGCGCUGCCUAGAAAGCCUUACAACAAAGGUCAAUACUUGGCAUUUAAUAAGAGCUCAGUAAAUCUUUGAUUUAGUUUUCCAAACAUCUCCAAAACUUCUUUUAAGCUACAGCAGCAAAAACCAUGUGCAGUCUUCUAACCACAAAAGGCAACAUGAGUUUUAAACAAAGUAAGGUAUUGUUUUCUGAUUUGUUUCAUUUCUGAUGCCCUUCCUGAAUAUGCCAGUUUUUUCUUAGCCUUUUUGGAUAAGUAGCAUAUUGAGUUAAUGUCUUCAAUGAAAAUAAAACUUCCACAUCCAAUCUUUCAGUCAUAAAUGAGUGCUAUCUGCACCAUCCGAUAGGGAUUGUUUUUCUUCUUAAUACCUUACCUAAUAUUGCUUCACCCUAAGUAAAGCUCAUUGGGAAAUUUCAUAUUCACUAAAGGCAACCAUAAGAUUUGGGGAAUCAUAUAAUCAAGAAUUGUAUAUAUCUAAAAAGGAACAUUAUAAAAUCCUUUAAUGCAGACCACUUAUAGUCCAACUUAAAGAUGAGGAAAUUGACUCUUAAAAAGAUUAAAUGACUCUUCCAAAAUCACAAAGAUAAUUCAGUGAUUUUUUUCCCCUACUAAAUGUUCCUUUUUUCUGCACUUCAUUCUCACUUAAGCAAUUUAUUGUCUAAAAUAGCAUCAUGGAAUGAUAUAAAAAUGCAGCUUUCCAAUCACACUAAGGGUCUCUCUAUUUCUUCUCUUGACCACCAAUCAGGAACCUUUGCUGGAAGCUUGUUUCUGAUUGGUGAAAGUAAGCCAUAACAGUGGAAUGCCAAGGAGUAAAUACAAAAGUGUAGCAACAACUGAGUUUGCUGUCUCACUACCCUCAGCCUAGGCCAACCUGGACUCCUUCACCCCAAAUGAGGUGACCGCUACAUUUUAUAUGAAGACACUGAUUUACCAUUCAACUGUGAUCCAUCUUAUAACAUGGCAAUCCAAUACAGACAGGAAGAUAAAACUCAACAACAGCUAAAAUAAAGUGUAUUCCCAGAAUACACAUUGCAGAAAAAGGAUGAAGUUGACCAGUGAAAAGUUGCCCAAGAACCCCUUUUAUGCCUCUGUAUCUCAGUAUGCUGCUAAAAACCAAAAAUUUUUCCAGUGGAAAAAGGAAAAGACUGAUUACACCCAUGCUAAUUUGGUGGAUAAGGCAUUGCAGCUCUUGAAGGAAAGAAUACUGAAAGGAGACACUCUGGCAUAUUUCCUACGAGGUCAACUAUAUUUUGAAGAGGGAUGGUAUGAAGAAGCAUUAGAACAGUUUGAAGAAAUCAAGGAGAAAGACCAUCAAGCAACUUACCAGCUAGGAGUGAUGUACUAUGAUGGGCUGGGGACCACUCUAGACGCUGAGAAAGGGGUGGACUAUAUGAAGAAAAUUCUUGAUUCUCCAUGUCCCAAAGCAAGACACUUAAAAUUUGCAGCUGCUUACAACCUCGGAAGAGCUUAUUAUGAAGGAAAAGGUGUUAAACGAUCAAAUGAGGAAGCUGAAAGACUGUGGCUUAUCGCAGCAGACAAUGGAAAUCCCAAAGCUAGUGUGAAGGCUCAAAGUAUGCUCGGGCUGUAUUACUCAACCAAGGAGCCCAAGGAGUUAGAAAAGGCAUUUUACUGGCAUUCCGAAGCAUGUGGCAAUGGGAAUCUGGAGUCCCAGGGUGCACUUGGGCUCAUGUACUUGUAUGGACAAGGCAUCCGGCAGGAUACGGAAGCUGCCCUGCAGUGCUUAAGAGAAGCAGCAGAACGCGGAAACGUCUAUGCUCAAGGGAAUCUCGUGGAGUAUUACUAUAAGAUGAAAUUUUUUACAAAGUGUGUUGCAUUUUCCAAAAGGAUCGCUGACUAUGAUGAGGUUCACGACAUCCCCAUGAUCGCCCAGGUCACAGACUGUCUCCCGGAGUUCAUCGGCAGAGGCAUGGCAAUGGCAUCCUUCUACCACGCAAGGUGUCUUCAGCUUGGCUUGGGCAUCACCAGGGAUGAAACAACCGCUAAACACUAUUAUUCUAAAGCUUGUCGUCUGAAUCCCGCAUUGGCAGAUGAACUUCACUCCUUACUUAUUCGUCAAAGAAUUUAGACCACAAUGUAUUUCAACAAAGAUCAUCAAUGCUAACACCUCACAAUGUGUGUAUUUUUACAGUAGCUAUGUUUGGUUAUUUUGCACAUCACAAAUUACACUAUCCUGGGUAUUUUACAGGUGACAUGUUACUUCGUUCUUGAAUUCGUACGCUGUUAAGUUUUGCAACUUGAAACCUAGACACAAGGUCAAAUUGCUGGAAGAGUCCUCAGAGGUCCACCUCUUACCCUACAGACUGGCCGAGACCAUAUCAAGUAUUAAAACCAUUCUAUACAGCAAGUAUCGUUUAUCCUUUCUUAAACACCGAGUCUCCAAAAAUACUUAGUUUAGCUUUAGUUUAGUAAGUUCAGAAGUAGAAACAAACUUAUUUAAAACCAUCAUUUGAAAGUUUAAUUCUUUAAAUUUGUCUCUUAGUUUUGUGAAUUUUGAAUAAUAAUGUUUAAAUUUUGUUUCAGUCAUUUAAAAUUUAAAUUUUCAGUCAUUUAAAAUUUUAAAAAUUUAAAAUUUCACAAAACUAAGGGUAAAAGACAUUUAAAGAAUUAAACUUAAAUAAGUGUGUGCAGCAUUUCUACUUCUGAAGUUAUUAAAGCUAAAACUGCACUAAGCCUUUUGAGACAUCCUUUAUUCUUAAAAAGCUCAUAAAUAAUUGGCUUAUUACAUAUAAACUUCAAAAAAGUGGGUUAUAAGACAUUGCUUUAGAAUCUUGCCCCUCCAAAUCUUCCCUCAAAGAUCUUAAUGAGUAAAACAACUGCUACAUACAUAUGCAGAAUGUGUAAUAAAACAAAAAGCAAUUGCUAUAUGAAAAUAUUCGUAAGAAAAGUAAAGCAAAUUGUUUCUUUGUGCUUCAGCUCAUUUUCCAUAUUUUUAAAACCCUGUGGUAAAAGCCUCAAUGAAAUCAUUUACAAGAACUACAAUUAAAUAUUGUUAAAAUUAGCAAAAGGCUUUCCGUAUAUAGAUGACAUCUAUGAAGGCAAAAGGUGACAGUAAAAACAGUAAGAUCCAUAUGCAUAAGAUUGUACAAGGCUAUUCAUUUGUGAAACAAAUAUACAUAUCGAAGACAGGUCUCAGAGAUACCUUAACUAUUCCUUUUUUUAUAAACAUAUUAAAGGAUGUGGCUUUAUUUUAUAAAUCACAACCAUCCCAACAGUGGAUUUAAACAAGAUUUCUUUUUAGUAAUGGGAAAAUGCAAUUAAUAUGGAGGUGAUAGUCACUAAGAACUGUUGAAUGGCAGAAAAGUAUUUGCUCUCGUUUUAUGUUCUGGCUUGUCUGUAUUGCCUGAACUUCAUUUUGUCUUUGUGUAAGGGAAGAAAUUUCAACAGACUCGGGUUUGAGAUAUCCUCAAAUGGUCAUGUAUUUCUGUCUCAAAUCUCUUAAUACCACCCAUGUAACAUUCCUUCAACCACUUGAAGAUCCAAAUUCCCAACUAGUAUUCUCUUCUCCACACUUAAUCCAGUUCCUAAAGAUUAUUAUUAUUAUUAUUAUUAUUAUUUUUUUUUUUUUGAGACGGAGUCUCCUGACCUAAUCUUAGCCCGGCGCAGUGGCUCACGUCUGUAAUCCCAGCACUUUGGGAGGCUGAGGCGGGCAGAUCAUGAGGUCAGGAGUUUGAGACCAGGCUGGCCAACGUGGUGAAACCCCGUCUCUACUAAAAAUACAAAAAUUAGCCGGGCGUGAUGGCGGACGCCUGUAGUCCCAGCUACUCGGGAGGCUGAGACAGAAGAACUGCUUGAAACCAGGAGGCAGAGGUUGCAGUGAGCUGAGAUCGCGCAAAUUGCACUCCAGCCUCGGUGACAAGAGCGAGACUCCAUCUCAAAAAAAAAUAAAAAGAAUCUUAAAAUAGGAACAUAAUAAAAGAUCGGCCCUAAGUAAAGAGCACUUUUUAAACUGCCAUUAAAGAUGGGUUUCAGAAAUCAUAAACUUUGACGUGUGCCAUACAUGGUAACAUGCUAUGCUUAUAUGUCUUCUAUAAAUCCAAUGCAGAAUUUAAAAUUUCAGUUUACUCUAGUUACCAUAAAGCUAAUGCUCUGGCACAAGCGAGUCCCUGCAAACUACCACUGCUGAGGACAGUAGUAAACCCCUUGACCUGAGACUGCGGUGAGUCUGUAACUCGAGUGCAUUGAGACUUCCAGAUCAUUACUCUUACACACACACACACACACACACAUACACACACACACACUCCUUCUCUAAGAUUCCUUGUAGCUGAUAUCUCAUGGAAAAAUGACAUUUUAUCAUAAAUAAAUAUAGAGACAAAAUAAUAGUGAUCUUUCUCAUUCGCAAUGUAAACUUAACAGCUACAGUUUAAAUGAUAGCAUAGAAUUAUGCCUAAAAUAGACAUUUCCCAUAAUUGUAUUGUGAUAAGUUCUUCAGGCUUGACAACUUCACAUUGCCUCUCUUCCUUGAAUGUAUUUUAUCUGGUCUUUUCUAUAUAGUCUUUUGAAGGAUAAUUUUUAUCAAUAGCCAACUUUGGGUAUUUUUUUAAGUGUCAAAUAUCAUCAUGGUUUGAAAAAAGGAUAAAAAAGCUAUAACUAAAAAAAUCUUAAGGAUAACAUUUGGUUUACUAAUUUUUAAUCAUUUAUCUUUCAGAACUUGUUUCUUAUCAAGAAGUUAGCAGGUAUGAUAUGUAUAUCAUACGUAUAUAAACUGGCAUAGGUUACAUCCUAGGGCAUGAGGGGAGUAUCUUUCAGGGAUUCAAAUGGAAUUUUUACCUGUUACUUGUUUAAUUGUUUUGUUUUCAAUAUUCUUGGGGAUUAGACAGGGGAAGGUAUUUUAUUACUGCAUAAUAGAUGGUGAAACCCAGGAAAAUUAAGUACUUGUGCAUGGCCCCACUAUCAAUAACACAAAGUCUGUACUCUGGAUCUCCCCUAAUGUCCCUGUGGUCUAAACGGCUUGAUAAUACAACCGAGCCCCUGAAGUAGCUGCCCUCCUCUUUCCGCUCCCCCAUCUCGGCCCUGCCCAUACUCCAAGGGUCAGCUCCCAUCUCUCCUCCCUAAUGCCUCACUUCAAGCACUAAUUUGGCUCUUUCUGCUCACUAAAAAUCAUAUAUUUUACAGAUUUAUUUUGUUUCUGGAGAAGGCAGCAAACUUUUACUUCCCUGCAGAAGUAGUUAAGUACAUAGUGUUUUCUCUAAAAAGGCAUUUGAUAAAUAUUUGAACAGCCUGUAGAGUUUCAACCUCUUUGAGAUAUAAGUAUCUUAAAUAUCAUAGAGCACUGUGAUUCAUUUUUAUAUUUUAUUGCUUUGAAUGCUCAAACUAUGGGAAAUCUUUGGUAAAAAUAAAGACAAUAAAAUCUUCACAAUAACUUUACACAAA